AGCCAAUUCUGACCGUGUCAACGAAUCAUCCACGCACCUGCAGCUCUGCUGAGAGAGUGCAAGCCGUGGGGUAAGAACCUUAGCUUUGUUUGUUGUAACUCUCAUUAAAAAGAUAUAAGGGCUGCAUGGGUAUUUUCUAAAAAGGAGAUAAUUUGAGCUAAUAUUGAGGGGAGGGAAGUAGGGUUAUUUAGAUUUUUAGUAUUUACUAUUUUGUCUAGAUUAAUGAUUAGUGACCUUGGGGCUAUUGAUCUGAGGAAUUUCUUGCAGAUGCUUGAGAGCGUGGGUUUCUUUUCACUGAUUGCGGAUCAAACCUGGUCAGCUCUUCUAUUCAGAUUGAACGGUCCUAUGCACUGUGGCAAGUUUUUUCUAGCUCUUAUUUCCCCACAGCGUAUGUUAACCUCUGCUGGAUGAAACCUUUGGCUAUUUAAGGCAUAUUUGUUGCUCCUUUACCCCGUUGAAAAGUUCUGCAUUUGUGUUACCUGUUUAAAAGUAGGGGCAGAUCUGAUGGAUCUUGUACAAUGCAGUUCUUAUUCCGUUUCCUUCAGAAGUGGACAAAGAGGGCCAUAUGUGGUUGCUGUAAAGAAGAGGAUGGUUAACAACCUGUGAGCAUUUGGUUUCUUGAUAAGCUUUCUCCCAGACCACCUACACUGAGCUAUUAAUUAGGAAUAGGAUGCACUUCGAGUUUUAUUUCAAUUCUUGUGAACUUAUAACUUUCCUAAGAAUAUAUUUAUACAUGUAGGCAAAGUCUCUUGAACUUUGUGGCACCUAGCAGAGUGUCCCACAGCAGCUGCAUGAAGCUUCAUAGACAGGGGCAUGGGGUGAGAAAGGAGGAAGUGGCCGCCAUGGCAGCUGGUCAGAUCAAUGGAUUCAACCUCAGUGAUUCGGUCCUUAGGAUGUCGUUACAUCUUAAGCCACCUCAUUUCAAGGUUUGAGGUGCCUUGCAUUUGGGUUUAGUUACCAUCCAGAAGGAACCAGACAGGUCUGGGUUCAAAUCUCUGCUUCUUCAGUUGGUCAUCUUGGGCAAGUUACUUUACCUCUGGGCUUUAGCUCCUCCAUCUGUAAAAUAUGAAUAAUAAUGGCCGCCAUUUUGUUGAGUCAUUGAGGGAUUAAACAAGGUAAUGGACAUAAAACACUUAGCUCCAUGUCAGACACGUAGGAAAUACUGAAAAGAAGUCAUUCUUACUCUUAUGUUGCAAAGAUCAUUCAACAUUCAAUAGGUUCUUAAUCUCUUUUCUAUUUCUUUAUAUCAUUGGGAAAAGAUAAAUUAGAUGAUUAAAUAUUCUUUGGUAAAACACUAGUUGUCAUUUGAUGAUGUCUUUUGACUUGGACUUUUAAAUUAUAAGAUAUUAAAGAUGUAUUAAGGAAGGUCAUUCUCUGUUUUUUACCUGCUUUUAACGUAGUAGUAGGGAUAUGAUAUUAACAUAUAUAUACUAUUUAUAGACUACAUCACCAACAUGGUGAAACCCCAUCUCUACUAAAAAUACAAAAAUUAGCCGGGUGUGAUGGCAGGUGCCUGUAAUCCCAGCUACUCAGGAGGCUGCGGCAGGAGAAUCGCUUGAACCUGGGAGGUGGAGCUUGCAGUGAGCUGAGAUCAUACCACUUUACUCCAGCCUGGGCAACAGAGCGAGACUCCAUCUCAAAAAAAAAAAAAAGUGUAUGUCCUACUUUUAAAAUUGCUUUAAUGAGGCCAAGCACAGUGGCUCACACCUCUAAUCACACCCAUUUGGGAGGCUGAGGUGGGAAGAUUGCUGGAGGCCAGGAGUUUAAGAGCAGCCUUGGCAACAUAGUGAGACCCUGUCUCUAUGUAAAAGUUGUUUUUAUAAAAUGUCAUAAUGCAUAAGUAUUGCCUGAGAGAUAGGACCUUUACUAUUGUUAUAUUAAGAGAAGUUCAAAAAGAGUUCCUCUCCCAUUGUAGUCCCAGAUAAGACUGUGGUAUUGGGCAGGGGGAAGAAGUGGGUAAGAGAUAGAAACUCUGACUUCUCAGCGCAGAGUUCCAGCUAAAGCAACUGGGUUAGAUUCUGCUGCAUUCUUAAGGGGCCAUGGCUCUAAGACCUAGAAGCUUAAAGUCAAUUGCUACAAAUUAAGCACUCUAUGAGAGGAUAACAUUAAAAGCACCUUUGUCAACCUAAUGAUUAUAACUGCCAGGGUCCUAUCAAGCCAUAAUAGAGCCUGAGGCAAAAGAAACAAUCAGCAAUACUGAUCCUGUCUUUAUGAAAAAUUUCGAUAUUUUGUUCAACAUAGAUUUUUGCAUUAAUUUUCAUUUUUAAAAAUAUUUCAUGUAAACAUUAUCUUGAUUACUGAGUUCCUUGGGACCCCCUUAACAUUUAUGCCUUCCUUGCUUCACCCGAGUCUUGACCUGAUAACUGCCACCAUUUAUUAAGUGUGAUAUGCUAGGCAUGGUACUAAGUGACUUACAUACAUUGUCUUAUGCCUCUUCACAAGCUCCAUUUUACAGAUGACAAAACCAGAUCUUUCAGAGAUUAAAUAAAUGGUCCGAGUACAUAGCUAAUGAGUGGAUGAAUGGUUAACAUUGGAUUUGAACACAGAUCCAUCAAUCACUAAAACCAAACUUAUUCUUUUUUUUUUUGAAACUGAGUCUUGCUCUGUUGCCCAGGCUGGAGUGCAGUGGUGGCAUCUCAGCUCACUGCAACCUCCACCUUUUGGGUUCAAGUGAUUAUCCUGCCUCAGCCUCCCGAGUAGCUGGGACUACAGGCACAUGCCACCACGCUCAGCUAAUUUUUUGUAUUUUUUUAGUAGAGACAGGGUUUCACCAUGUUAGCCAGGAUGGUCUUGAUCUCCUUACUUUGUGAUCCACCUGCCUCAGCCUCCCAAAGUGCUGGGAUUACAGGCCUGAGCCACCGCGCCAGGCCUACCAAACUCAUUCUUCAACCAUCAUGCCCUGCACUGUAUCAGGAAUUCACAACAUAAAUUCAUUCAUUCAACACAUAUUUAUGAGAGCAUAUUAUGCAUCACGUUGUACUAAGGAUUAAAACGUUGAAAUUCAUACAUACAAGGAUUCAUUCAUUCAUAUGUGCAUUCAACAAGCAGUAAUGAGCAGGCACCAUGUGUCAAGCACUAUGCUACAUGCUGAGGAUACAGAAGUGAACAAGACAGACAGCUACCACGGGAAUGAACAGAGAAGGGACAGGUGACAAGCAAAUGAAUGAAAGUUUAUUUACUAAGAGGUCAUUCAGAAGAGAUCAUGAAUUCAUGGAAAAUUAUUUUCUGCAUCUAGUGGCAUGGAAAUUAAGAUAUUCUGAAUUUUAAUGUAUAGUUUUAAGAAAACUGAAAGAAAAUAUAAAGUUUAUCAUUAUACAUUGGAUACUAUGAACACAAUAAUUUGAGUAGUAAUUACACUUCCAGGCCACAGUUGUAAACUGAUUUUCUAUUAGAAAUAUUUAAAAGUAGAUGUAGAAAACUUACUCUUAAAUAUAUAACAGUUCAAAAAUCCAGCAGGAACUAAGUUAAUUAAAUAGAAUAUUCACCUGUUUUUUCUGAUAAUUAUCCUGUGUUAUAUUUACAUAUUAAUGCAGUAUAAUAUUUUAGUAUACAUUACACUCUAGGGAGUCACUGAAAUGUCAGCAAAGAAAAAUACGGCCGGAGGCAUCUUAAGUCAUUUGACCACGUUUUUAAAAGUUGGUGUUUUGAGAAAUCAUCUAAAUGUGGUGACCUUACCAAAAUGAUUGCUUUUUCUCCAAGAUAUUUGAGAACACUUACCAGAAACAAUAGUUUAUGAAAUAUAAAAAUUAUAUGAUCAAUGUGGAUAAUUAAUAUUUUUACAAAGGAAUUCUCCAAGUUUACAUUGUAAGGGAGUUCACACAAAGAAACUAUGAUCAUAUGUGUUCCCAAGAUAAGAGAUAAGAUGCUCUCUCUCCUUUACUAGUAUCAGCAGCUAAUGGAAAACUUGGGAGUGGCCCUCUCACUCCCUACUCUCCAUAGGUUUUCUGGAAUUUCUUCACUUCAAGAAAAAAACCAGACUUGGGAAGGUUCUAGAGAAAGAGAAAUACAGAUGAGAGAGAGGUAACAUUCUAAGUGGCCUUAUGUUUUGAUUCUGCCCCACCUUUGUUACCCUGCCAUGUUUGUGUGCAUUCCUGUGGAUGGGCGUGCCCACUGCCUCCCUCACCUCCCAUCCAGGCUUUCAGAAUGAUGGGAACAUGACACGCACAGAGAAUUCUCUCUAACCCAUCCUCUUUCUGUUGAGCAUAUCUUUUGCUCCCUCUGCUUGUCUAUGGGAGUGACCUGUCUGAGGGAGGUUGAGGGUCAAUGUGUAACAGAUACAUACAAAUGGAAGCAGAAAAACUCCCCCACUAACUUAUCACCUGCUCUUGGUGCCUUCAGAGAGCCUGGUGUGGGGACACGUAGAGUUAAAUUGUUUACUAAUUUGAAAUUAGAAUCUAACCACUUCUCUCCACUUCCAUUGAUACAUUCUCUCUGGCACAAGUUACGCUAUAGUGUCCCAAGGAGUCUUCCCUGCCAGCCUUGUGGCUCCCAGUCAUUUCCACCCAACAAACAGAGGAAUCUUUUUAUUUGUUUGUUUGUUUAUUUAUUUAUUUAUUUAUUUUAUACUGUAAGUUCUGGGGUACAUGUGCGGAACGUGCAUGUUUGUUACAUAGGUAUACACAUGCCAUGGUGGUUUGCUGCACCCAUCAGCCCAUCAUCUACAUUAGGUAUUUCUCCUAAUGCUAUUCCUCCCCUAGCCCCCCACCCCCUGACAGGCCCCGGUGUGUGUCAAUGUGUUCUCAUUGUUCAACUCCCAGUUAUGAGUGAGAACAUGUGGUGUUUGGUUUUCUGUUCUUGUAUUAGUUUGCUGAGAAUGAUGGUUUCCAGAUUCAUCCAUGUCCCUGCAAAGGACAUGAACACAUUCUUUUUUAUGGCUGCAUAGUAUUCCAUGGUGUAUAUGUGCCAUAUUUUCUUUAUCCAGUCUAUCAUUGAUGGGCAUUUGGGUUGGUUCCAAGUCUUUGCUGUUGUGAAUAGUGCUGCAAUAAACACGUGUGUGCAUGUAUCUUUAUAGUAGAAUGAUUUAUAAUCCUUUGGAUAGAUACCCAGUAAUGGCAUUGCAGGAUCAAAUAGUAUUUCUAGUUCUAGAUCCUUGAGGAAUCGCCACAUUGUCUUCCACAAUUGUUGAGCUAAUUUACACCCCCACCAACAGUGUAAAAGCGUUCCUAUUUCUCUACACCCUCUCCAGCACCUGUUGUCUCCUGACUUUUUAAUGAUCACCAUUCUAACAGGCAUGAGAUGGUAUCUCAUUGUGGUUUUGAUUUGCAUUUCUCUAAUGACCAGUGAUCAUGAGCUUUUUUUCAUAUGUUUGUUGGCUGCAUAAAUGUCUUCUUUUGAGAAGUGCCUGUUCAUAUCCUUCACCCACUUUUUGAUGGGGUUGUUUUUUUCUUGUAAAUUUUUUAAUGUUCUUUAUAGAUUCUGGGUAUUAGCCCUUUGUCAGAUGGACAGAUUGCAAAAAUUUUCUCCCAUUCUAUAGGUUGCCUCAAACAGAGGAAUCUUUAAAAUGUAUGUCAGAACCUGUCAUUCCUGGACUCUAAAUCUUCUGCUGGUUUCUUAUUUCAGUCAGAGGAAAAUUGCCAAGUUCUUAUAAGAUCCGACCUCUUCUCUGAUUCCGUCCCCUAACUCCACUCCAGGUCUUCCUCACAUUUUCCAAGCACAUCAGGAUCUUUAAAUUUGUACUUGCUGUUCUCUCUCUCUCCAAAAUACUCUUUCCCCAGACAACAAGUGUCUUGCUUCUUUGGCCCCUUUAGAUUUCUGCAUGAAGAUCACUAUCAGGGAGGCCAUUUUUGAUCAUUCUAUAAAAAAGAAAAUCACUCCCCAGUCUCUCUCUGUUUCCCUUAUCUUAGUUAUUUUUCCUUCAAGACAAUAUCACUGCCUGAUAUUGGUCCCCACCCAAAUCUCAUCUUGAACUGUAGCUCCCAUAAUUCCCACAUGUUGUGGGAGGGACCUGGUGGGAAGUAAUUGAAUCAUGGGGGCGGGUCUUUCCCAUGCUGUUCUCAUGAUAGUGAAUAAGUCUCAUGAGAUCUGGUGGUUUUAUAAAGAGGAGGUUCCCUGCACAUGCUCUCUUGCCUGCUGCCACAUAAGACAUGACUUUGCUCCUCAUUCGCCUUCCACCAUGAUUGUGAGGCCUCCCCAGGCAUGUGGAAUUGUGAGUCAUAACAUAUAAACGUAUUGUUUUGUUUGCAGUCUCUCUUUUCUUAACUUCUUUCUAGAAUAUAAGCUAUGUAGAAACAGAAAUCUCUUCUGUUCACUGCUACUUCCCCAGUGCCUAGAAAAGUUUCUGGCAGAAUAGGUACUUAAUAAAUAUCUUGAAUAAUGAAUAUCGUAAAAUCUUAGUACUCCAACUACCUCUGUUCUACGUCUAAUCCAACCACGUGAAGCCUGGCACAUCUCCCAAAGUCCUCAGAAUUCUAUAUCCUUCAAUUUCCUCAUCUAUCAAAUGGGAGUAGUAGUACUUCCCUCACAGAGUAUGGUGAUAAAUAAAUGAGAUAAUAUACAUGAAGCAAUUAGUAUGUAUCUUGGCACAUUGAAAUCUAACCUGAAAGCUUUGAUUCUAUGCCAUAACAGAAUUCAGCAGCUGAAUAUCAAGACCUUUGAAUUCAACAAGAAGUUAAGACAUUUAUAGUUGUCUAACAACAGACUGAAGAUUGUGGCUUGGUAUUCACUGGCAGGUUUCAGACAUUUAGAUCUUUCUUUUAAUGACUAACACCAUGCCUAUCUGUGGAGAAGCUGGCAACAUGUCACACCUGGAAAUUGUUUUUCAACAUUAAUACUAUUAUUUGGCAGUAAUCCAGAUUGCUUUUGCCACCAACCUGAAGACAUAUAGAGGCAGAAGGACAGGAAUAAUUCUAUUUGUUUCCUGUUUUGAAACUUCCAUCUGUAAGGUAAGUGUUGAAAGUCAGAUAUUGGCUCCAGGGACUUUCUAUAUCCACAAAUACAAAAAUUGAGGGGUAACUCCUUGAUAUCAAGUCAAAGGCUCACAAUGUCUGGUAAUAAAACAAAUUACUUUCAAUUUUCUUGAAAUCUUCAGGCUAUCAAAAGGAGAUGUGAGAGAGGGUAUUGAGUCUGGCCUGACAAUGCAGUUCUUAAACCAAAGGUCCAUUAUGCUUCUCCUCUCUGAGAAUCCUGACUUACCUCAACAACGGAGACAUGGCACAGUAGCCAGCUUGGAGACUUCUCAGCCAAUGCUCUGAGAUCAAGUCGAAGACCCAAUAUACAGGGUUUUGAGCUCAUCUUCAUCAUUCAUAUGAGGAAAUAAGUGGUAAAAUCCUUGGAAAUACAAUGAGACUCAUCAGAAACAUUUACAUAUUUUGUAGUAUUGUUAUGACAGCAGAGGGUGAUGCUCCAGAGCUGCCAGAAGAAAGGGAACUGAUGACCAACUGCUCCAACAUGUCUCUAAGAAAGGUUCCCGCAGACUUGACCCCAGCCACAACGACACUGGAUUUAUCCUAUAACCUCCUUUUUCAACUCCAGAGUUCAGAUUUUCAUUCUGUCUCCAAACUGAGAGUUUUGAUUCUAUGCCAUAACAGAAUUCAACAGCUGGAUCUCAAAACCUUUGAAUUCAACAAGGAGUUAAGAUAUUUAGAUUUGUCUAAUAACAGACUGAAGAGUGUAACUUGGUAUUUACUGGCAGGUCUCAGGUAUUUAGAUCUUUCUUUUAAUGACUUUGACACCAUGCCUAUCUGUGAGGAAGCUGGCAACAUGUCACACCUGGAAAUCCUAGGUUUGAGUGGGGCAAAAAUACAAAAAUCAGAUUUCCAGAAAAUUGCUCAUCUGCAUCUAAAUACUGUCUUCUUAGGAUUCAGAACUCUUCCUCAUUAUGAAGAAGGUAGCCUGCCCAUCUUAAACACAACAAAACUGCACAUUGUUUUACCAAUGGACACAAAUUUCUGGGUUCUUUUGCGUGAUGGAAUCAAGACUUCAAAAAUAUUAGAAAUGACAAAUAUAGAUGGCAAAAGCCAAUUUGUAAGUUAUGAAAUGCAACGAAAUCUUAGUUUAGAAAAUGCUAAGACAUCGGUUCUAUUGCUUAAUAAAGUUGAUUUACUCUGGGACGACCUUUUCCUUAUCUUACAAUUUGUUUGGCAUACAUCAGUGGAACACUUUCAGAUCCGAAAUGUGACUUUUGGUGGUAAGGCUUAUCUUGACCACAAUUCAUUUGACUACUCAAAUACUGUAAUGAGAACUAUAAAAUUGGAGCAUGUACAUUUCAGAGUGUUUUACAUUCAACAGGAUAAAAUCUAUUUGCUUUUGACCAAAAUGGACAUAGAAAACCUGACAAUAUCAAAUGCACAAAUGCCACACAUGCUUUUCCCGAAUUAUCCUACGAAAUUCCAAUAUUUAAAUUUUGCCAAUAAUAUCUUAACAGACGAGUUGUUUAAAAGAACUAUCCAACUGCCUCACUUGAAAACUCUCAUUUUGAAUGGCAAUAAACUGGAGACACUUUCUUUAGUAAGUUGCUUUGCUAACAACACACCCUUGGAACACUUGGAUCUGAGUCAAAAUCUAUUACAACAUAAAAAUGAUGAAAAUUGCUCAUGGCCAGAAACUGUGGUCAAUAUGAAUCUGUCAUACAAUAAAUUGUCUGAUUCUGUCUUCAGGUGCUUGCCCAAAAGUAUUCAAAUACUUGACCUAAAUAAUAACCAAAUCCAAACUGUACCUAAAGAGACUAUUCAUCUGAUGGCCUUACGAGAACUAAAUAUUGCAUUUAAUUUUCUAACUGAUCUCCCUGGAUGCAGUCAUUUCAGUAGACUUUCAGUUCUGAACAUUGAAAUGAACUUCAUUCUCAGCCCAUCUCUGGAUUUUGUUCAGAGCUGCCAGGAAGUUAAAACUCUAAAUGCGGGAAGAAAUCCAUUCCGGUGUACCUGUGAAUUAAAAAAUUUCAUUCAGCUUGAAACAUAUUCAGAGGUCAUGAUGGUUGGAUGGUCAGAUUCAUACACCUGUGAAUACCCUUUAAACCUAAGGGGAACUAGGUUAAAAGACGUUCAUCUCCACGAAUUAUCUUGCAACACAGCUCUGUUGAUUGUCACCAUUGUGGUUAUUAUGCUAGUUCUGGGGUUGGCUGUGGCCUUCUGCUGUCUCCACUUUGAUCUGCCCUGGUAUCUCAGGAUGCUAGGUCAAUGCACACAAACAUGGCACAGGGUUAGGAAAACAACCCAAGAACAACUCAAGAGAAAUGUCCGAUUCCACGCAUUUAUUUCAUACAGUGAACAUGAUUCUCUGUGGGUGAAGAAUGAAUUGAUCCCCAAUCUAGAGAAGGAAGAUGGUUCUAUCUUGAUUUGCCUUUAUGAAAGCUACUUUGACCCUGGCAAAAGCAUUAGUGAAAAUAUUGUAAGCUUCAUUGAGAAAAGCUAUAAGUCCAUCUUUGUUUUGUCUCCCAACUUUGUCCAGAAUGAGUGGUGCCAUUAUGAAUUCUACUUUGCCCACCACAAUCUCUUCCAUGAAAAUUCUGAUCAUAUAAUUCUUAUCUUACUGGAACCCAUUCCAUUCUAUUGCAUUCCCACCAGGUAUCAUAAACUGAAAGCUCUCCUGGAAAAAAAAGCAUACUUGGAAUGGCCCAAGGAUAGGCGUAAAUGUGGGCUUUUCUGGGCAAACCUUCGAGCUGCUAUUAAUGUUAAUGUAUUAGCCACCAGAGAAAUGUAUGAACUGCAGACAUUCACAGAGUUAAAUGAAGAGUCUCGAGGUUCUACAAUCUCUCUGAUGAGAACAGAUUGUCUAUAAAAUCCCACAGUCCUUGGGAAGUUGGGGACCACAUACACUGUUGGGAUGUACAUUGAUACAACCUUUAUGAUGGCAAUUUGACAAUAUUUAUUAAAAUAAAAAAUGGUUAUUCCCUUCAUAUCAGUUUCUAGAAGGAUUUCUAAGAAUGUAUCCUAUAGAAACACCUUCACAAGUUUAUAAGGGCUUAUGGAAAAAGGUGUUCAUCCCAGGAUUGUUUAUAAUCAUGAAAAAUGUGGCCAGGUGCAGUGGCUCACUCUUGUAAUCCCAGCACUAUGGGAGGCCAAGGUGGGUGACCCACGAGGUCAAGAGAUGGAGACCAUCCUGGCCAACAUGGUGAAACCCUGUCUCUACUAAAAAUACAAAAAUUAGCUGGGCGUGAUGGUGCACGCCUGUAGUCCCAGCUACUUGGGAGGCUGAGGCAGGAGAAUCGCUUGAACCCGGGAGGUGGCAGUUGCAGUGAGCUGAGAUCGAGCCACUGCACUCCAGCCUGGUGACAGAGCGAGACUCCAUCUCAAAAAAAAGAAAAAAAAAAAAGAAAAAAAUGGAAAACAUCCUCAUGGCCACAAAAUAAGGUCUAAUUCAAUAAAUUAUAGUACAUUAAUGUAAUAUAAUAUUACAUGCCACUAAAAAGAAUAAGGUAGCUGUAUAUUUCCUGGUAUGGAAAAAACAUAUUAAUAUGUUAUAAACUAUUAGGUUGGUGCAAAACUAAUUGUGGUUUUUGCCAUUGAAAUGGCAUUGAAAUAAAAGUGUAAAGAAAUCUAUACCAGAUGUAGUAACAGUGGUUUGGGUCUGGGAGGUUGGAUUACAGGGAGCAUUUGAUUUCUAUGUUGUGUAUUUCUAUAAUGUUUGAAUUGUUUAGAAUGAAUCUGUAUUUCUUUUAUAAGUAGAAAAAAAAUAAAGAUAGUUUUUACAGCCUA